AAAACAGGGAAAGCCGGAGUUAGGCAACAGAGUGCCUAGCUUUCUCAGUCAUUCAAACACAAGCACGGAAGAAGAGAUUGCACUGACCAGAGGACCGCCAGGGUGUGAUGCUCCGUAGUCGCAGGGAUGAAGGAAAACCAUGGGCGGAGCUUGUCAUGGACAGCUCCUAGGUGGACAUAAAUGGAAACUCAUUGGUUCUGGGGCACGGCGGGAAGAGGGAGACGGCCCUGGACGGCCGCACCAAGAAUUUCACAACCCAAACCCGACUAGAAAGCCUGGGGCUCCCAAUAUUACAAGUCUGUUCUUGACAAGGAAGUUGGGAUGACAGAACUACUGUAUGAAAACUCAGAAAUGCUCAGAAGUGCAGACCUUUGGUUCUGUUUUCUUCCUCAUCAGAUAGGAAUUUUUUUUAACUACGCACAGAAUCACACUUGCGAAGUCUUCUUUUCCUUCUUGUUACUUUAUUUAGAAGCUGUGAACUCAAGAAGUAGGUCCCAUGUUGAAUCUACAUGUGCGCAGGUGAUUCUUUUAGCCAAGUCAUUUCCACACUCAUGCCCAAGUCUGGAGAUACACAGGAUUUUAAGCUCAACGGUUAUCAGCUCAAAAGCAGAAAAUGUUCAUUCCCGUUUGUGCCCUGGUAUCUUGAAGAAUGUGCAAUAGGUUAUGGCCACACCGUGCCCUUGUCAGAUGGAGGUAAGGCCUUCUGCAUCAUCUACUCCGUCAUUGGCAUUCCCUUCACCCUCCUGUUCCUGACGGCUGUGGUCCAGCGCAUCACCGUGCACGUCACCCGCAGGCCGGUCCUCUACUUCCACAUCCGCUGGGGCUUCUCCAAGCAGGUGGUGGCCAUCGUCCAUGCCGUGCUCCUUGGGUUUGUCACUGUGUCCUGCUUCUUCUUCAUCCCGGCCGCUGUCUUCUCAGUCCUGGAGGAUGACUGGAACUUCCUGGAAUCCUUUUAUUUUUGUUUUAUUUCCCUGAGCACCAUUGGCCUGGGGGAUUAUGUGCCUGGGGAAGGCUACAAUCAAAAAUUCAGAGAGCUCUAUAAGAUUGGGAUCACGUGUUACCUGCUACUUGGCCUUAUUGCCAUGUUGGUAGUUCUGGAAACCUUCUGUGAACUCCAUGAGCUGAAAAAAUUCAGAAAAAUGUUCUAUGUGAAGAAGGACAAGGACGAGGAUCAGGUGCACAUCAUAGAGCAUGACCAACUGUCCUUCUCCUCGAUCACAGACCAGGCAGCUGGCAUGAAAGAGGACCAGAAGCAAAAUGAGCCUUUUGUGGCCACCCAGUCAUCUGCCUGCGUGGAUGGCCCUGCAAACCAUUGAGCGUAGGAUUUGUUGCAUUAUGCUAGAGCACCAGGGUCAGGGUGCAAGGAAGAGGCUUAAGUAUGUUCAUUUUUAUCAGAAUGCAAAAGCGAAAAUUAUGUCACUUUAAGAAAUAGCUACUGUUUGCAAUGUCUUAUUAAAAAACAACAAAAAAAGACAAAUGGAACAAAGAAGCUGUGACCCCAGCAGGAUGUCUAAUAUGUGAGGAAAUGAGAUGUCCACCUAAAAUUCAUAUGUGACAAAAUUAUCUCGACCUUACAUAGGAGGAGAAUACUUGAAGCAGUAUGCUGCUGUGGUUAGAAGCAGAUUUUAUACUUUUAACUGGAAACUUUGGGGUUUGCAUUUAGAUCAUUUAGCUGAUGGCUAAAUAGCAAAAUUUAUAUUUAGAAGCAAAAAAAAAAAGCAUAGAGAUGUGUUUUAUAAAUAGGUUUAUGUGUACUGGUUUGCAUGUACCCACCCAAAAUGAUUAUUUUUGUAGAAUCUAAGUUAAACUUACUAUUUAUAAUGCAUAGGUAACCAUUAACUAUGUACAUAUAAAGUAUAAAUAUGUUUAUAUUCUGUACAUAUGGUUUAGGUCACCAGAUCCUAGUGUAGUUCUGAAACUAAGACUAUAGAUAUUUUGUUUCUUUUGAUUUCUCUUUAUACUAAAGAAUCCAGAGUUGCUACAAUAAAAUAAGGGGAAUAAUAAACUUGAGAGUGAAUAACCAUAGUAUUCUGCUGCAAUAAAUGUUUCUACCCUCUUGCGAUAGAAUGGUGUCAGAUGUCUAACAUGUUUAUAAACAUUUUUUUGAAUUGAACAGGUUAUGAAAAGGAUUUAUUAAAAGGUUAAGAUACUUUGUUUUGAAAGUACAUUGUGAUUUGCAGCCACCUAGCACUAAAGCAUAGAACUUAAACACGAAUCCCUAAAUGAACAGAUUAUGUUACAUUAAUCUGAGAAUUUUAAAUUUAGAAGCUAAAAUAAAUAAAAAUCACAGCUGGUUGUAA